AAGUGUUCGCUACGCGGGGCUACCGGAUCGGUCGGAAAUGGCAGAGGUGGAGGAGACACUGAAGCGACUGCAGAGCCAGAAGGGAGUGCAGGGAAUCAUCGUCGUGAACACAGAAGGCAUUCCCAUCAAGAGCACCAUGGACAACCCCACCACCACCCAGUAUGCCAGCCUCAUGCACAGCUUCAUCCUGAAGGCACGGAGCACCGUGCGUGACAUCGACCCCCAGAACGAUCUCACCUUCCUUCGAAUUCGCUCCAAGAAAAAUGAAAUUAUGGUUGCACCAGGUAAGGGGUCUUCUACCUCCCCAUGUAGGAACAGACCUCAUGGCACAUUCUCUGUGGCUCAUCAGGAGUCCUGGCACAGUGGUGUCUCCAGAGGAUCCAAGCAGGGCCCGAGGAGUUGAAGGAAUUGGGUUGUUGCCUCACUGCCUAGCCAGCCUCCAGCUGGUGUCCCAUAGCAGAUCCUCCCAGGGACCGGCCCCAGAGGGUAACCCCAGUCUCCUGAGAUAGACAGACACGUGAGCAUCAUGUGUGUCUCCCCUUCCUUGAUAGGAGAAAACUCAAAGGCAUUUGGGACAUAGAGGAGGGUGUGGCCAGGCCUGUCUGGGGCUGUCUGCAAAAGCUUCCCAGAAGAGGGGACACUGGAGCUGAAUCUUAAGGGCACCAGGAAGCAGUGUGAGCAAGGCGGAGGGGCGGAAAGCCACGUUUGGAAGAAUAUUCAGUGAUUCUUCUCCAAAAUGUAAAGCAAAAGUACUGUAUCAUUUUAUCCUUGAAAACAUGUUCUCUGCCCACUUGUAAAGGCCAGGCCUGUCUUUAGGCCCCUUACAGCCAGCUUUUCCUGCCGCACGGGAGCAGAUUGCUUUGUUUCCUUUACGCGAGGUGCUUGCCUUGCAUUUGGGGGCUCUGUGGUGCAACCAAGGCCUGUGUUUAGUCCUUAGGAUCAUUCUCAGGGUGAGGAGAUGCUCAUUCUGGGAGGAGCCCACAAGGAUGGGAGCACAGGAGCGAGCAACAGAGCCACAUCUCCUGCCCGGCUCCCUCGCUCUCACUCAUGGACUGGGGUGGCAGGCAGAGCCUCCA